ACAGAGCUCAGGACAGGGCUGAGGAACCAUGUCUCCAUCCCCGACCGCCCUCUUCUGUCUUGGGCUGUGUCUGGGGCGUGUGCCAGCGCAGAGUGGACCGCUCCCCAAGCCCUCCCUCCAGGCUCUGCCCAGCUCCCUGGUGCCCCUGGAGAAGCCAGUGACCCUCCGGUGCCAGGGACCUCCGGGCGUGGACCUGUACCGCCUGGAGAAGCUGAGUUCCAGCAGGUACCAGGAUCAGGCAGUCCUCUUCAUCCCGGCCAUGAAGAGAAGUCUGGCUGGACGCUACCGCUGCUCCUACCAGAACGGAAGCCUCUGGUCCCUGCCCAGCGACCAGCUGGAGCUCGUUGCCACGGGAGUUUUUGCCAAACCCUCGCUCUCAGCCCAGCCCGGCCCGGCGGUGUCGUCAGGAGGGGACGUAACCCUACAGUGUCAGACUCGGUAUGGCUUUGACCAAUUUGCUCUGUACAAGGAAGGGGACCCUGCGCCCUACAAGAAUCCCGAGAGAUGGUACAGGGCUAGUUUUCCCAUCAUCACGGUGACCGCCGCCCACAGCGGAACCUACCGAUGCUACAGCUUCUCCAGCAGGGACCCAUACCUGUGGUCAGCCCCCAGCGACCCCCUGGAGCUUGUGGUCACAGGAACCUCUGUGACCCCCAGCCGGUUACCAACAGAACCACCUUCCCCGGUAGCAGAAUUCUCAGAAGCCACCGCUGAACUGACCGUCUCAUUCACAAACGAAGUCUUCACAACUGAGACUUCUAGGAGUAUCACCGCCAGUCCAAAGGAGUCAGACUCUCCAGCUGGUGAGUCCUGCCCGCCAGUACUACACCAAGGGCAACCUGGUCCGGAUAUGCCUCGGGGCUGUGAUCCUAAUAAUCCUGGCGGGGUUUCUGGCAGAGGACUGGCACAGCCGGAGGAAGCGCCUGCGGCACAGGGGCAGGGCUGUGCAGAGGCCGCUUCCGCCCCUCCCGCCCCUCCCGCUGACCCGGAAAUCAAACGGGGGUCAGGAUGGAGGCCGACAGGAUGUUCACAGCCGCGGGUUAUGUUCAUGACCGCUGAACCCCAGGCACGGUCGUAUCCAAGGGAGGGAUCAUGGCAUGGGAGGCGACUCAAAGACUGGCGUGUGUGGAGCGUGGAAGCAGGAGGGCAGAGGCUACAGCUGUGGAAACGAGGCCAUGCUGCCUCCUCCUGGUGUUCCAUCAGGGAGCCGUUCGGCCAGUGUCUGUCUGUCUGUCUGCCUCUCUGUCUGAGGGCACCCUCCAUUUGGGAUGGAAGGAAUCUGUGGAGACCCCAUCCUCCUCCCUGCACACUGUGGAUGACAUGGUACCCUGGCUGGACCACAUACUGGCCUCUUUCUUCAACCUCUCUAAUAUGGGCUCCAGACGGAUCUCUAAGGUUCCCAGCUCUCAGGGUUGACUCUGUUCCAUCCUCUGUGCAAAAUCCUCCCGUGCUUCCCUUUGGCCCUCUGUGCUCUUGUCUGGUUUUCCCCAGAAACUCUCACCCUCACUCCAUCUCCCACUGCGGUCUAACAAAUCUCCUUUCGUCUCUCAGAACGGGUCUUGCAGGCAGUUUGGGUAUGUCAUUCAUUUUCCUUAGUGUAAAACUAGCACGUUGCCCGCUUCCCUUCACAUUAGAAAACAAGAUCAGCCUGUGCAACAUGGUGAAACCUCAUCUCUACCAACAAAACAAAAAAACACAAAAAUUAGCCAGGUGUGGUGGUGCAUCCCUAUACUCCCAGCAACUCAGGGGGCUGAGGUGGGAGAAUGGCUUGAGCCUGGGAGGCAGAGGUUGCAGUGAGCUGAGAUCACACCACUGCACUCUAGCUCGGGUGACGAAGCCUGACUUUGUCUCAAAAAAUACAGGGAUGAAUAUGUCAAUUACCCUGAUUUGAUCAUAGCACGUUGUAUACAUGUACUGCAAUAUUGCUGUCCACCCCAUAAAUAUGUACAAUUCUGUAUACAUUUUUAAAAUCAUAAAAAUAAGAUAAUGCACCGUCUCCACCCCUCUCAUAUUUACUUUCUGAAGGAAAUGUUAGGUCUUCUCAAGGUAAAGUUCUAUAUUUAUUAUAGCGUUUAGGCAUUUCUUGACCAUCUAAUGAGUGUAAAACUGUACCACUGGGCCAAGUGCAGUGGAUCAUGUCUGUAAUCCUAGCACUGUGGGAGGCCAAGGCAGGAGGAUCGCUUGAGCCCAGGAGUUCAAGACCAGCCUGGGCAACAUAGUGAGACCCCAUCUCUACUUAAAAUAAAGAAGAUAAAAAUUGUUUUAAAA